AGUUCUGUUUCUUUCCUGCGUUGAUCUUGGACAGUAACUGUACUAUGUAAGGAAUUGUCGGUGGCUGGCGACGGUAUCUUAGCUGGUUUUCAGAAACCCUCAUUCCUCCCUUGACUGAUUCACCACUUGAACCUCAUAUGACGUAGAAGAAGCCUACCUAUGUCCCCUUCACAUGUUGUGGUCAAUGUGUCAACUGCACGAUCCGGGCCCCUCACCACAUCCUCUGCACCGGUCAGUCGAGCCGAGUCACUGCGUCCUGGCAGCAGAAGCUGCACCAUGUCCAUGUCACCCACGGUCAUCAUCCUGGCAUGUCUUGGGUUCUUCUUGGACCAGAGUGUGUGGGCACACGUGGGUGGUCAGGACAAGCCCUUCUGCUCUGCCUGGCCCAGCGCUGUGGUGCCUCAAGGAGGACACGUGACUCUUCGGUGUCACUGUCGUCGUGGGUUUAACAUCUUCACGCUGUACAAGAAAGAUGGGGUCCCUGUCCCUGAGCUCUACAACAGAAUAUUCUGGAACAGUUUCCUCAUUAGCCCUGUGACCCCAGCACACGCAGGGACCUACAGAUGUCGAGGUUUUCACCCGCACUCCCCCACUGAGUGGUCGGCACCCAGCAACCCCCUGGUGAUCAUGGUCACAGGUCUAUAUGAGAAACCUUCGCUUACAGCCCGGCCGGGCCCCACGGUUCGCGCAGGAGAGAACGUGACCUUGUCCUGCAGCUCCCAGAGCUCCUUUGACAUCUACCAUCUAUCCAGGGAGGGGGAAGCCCAUGAACUUAGGCUCCCUGCAGUGCCCAGCAUCAAUGGAACAUUCCAGGCCGACUUCCCUCUGGGUCCUGCCACCCACGGAGAGACCUACAGAUGCUUCGGCUCUUUCCAUGGAUCUCCCUACGAGUGGUCAGACCCGAGUGACCCACUGCCUGUUUCUGUCACAGGAAACCCUUCUAGUAGUUGGCCUUCACCCACUGAACCAAGCUUCAAAACUGGUAUCGCCAGACACCUGCAUGCUGUGAUUAGGUACUCAGUGGCCAUCAUCCUCUUCACCAUCCUUCCCUUCUUUCUCCUUCAUCGCUGGUGCUCCAAAAAAAAAAAUGCUGCUGUAAUGAACCAAGAGCCUGCGGGACACAGAACAGUGAACAGGGAGGACUCUGAUGAACAAGACCCUCAGGAGGUGACAUACGCACAGUUGGAUCACUGCAUUUUCACACAGAGAAAAAUCACUGGCCCUUCUCAGAGGAGCAAGAGACCCUCAACAGAUACCAGCGUGUGUAUAGAACUUCCAAAUGCUGAGCCCAGAGCGUUGUCUCCUGCCCAUGAGCACCACAGUCAGGCCUUGAUGGGAUCUUCUAGGGAGACAACAGCCCUGUCUCAAACCCAGCUUGCCAGCUCUAAUGUACCAGCAGCUGGAAUCUGAAGGCGUGAGUCUCCAUCUUAGAGCAUCACUCUUCCUCACACCACAAAUCUGGUGCCUGUCUCUUGCUUACCAAUGUCUAAGGUCCCCACUGCCUGCUGCAGAGAAAACACACUCCUUUGCUUAGCCCACAAUUCUCUAUUUCACUUGACCCCUGCCCACCUCUCCAACCUAACUGGCUUACUUCCUAGUCUACUUGAGGCUGCAAUCACACUGAGGAACUCACAAUUCCAAACAUACAAGAGGCUCUCUCUUAACACGGCACUUAGACACGUGCUGUUCCACCUUCCCUCGUGCUGUUCCACCUUUCCUCAGACUAUUUUUCAGCCUUCUGGCAUCAGCAAACCUUAUAAAAUUUUUUUGAUUUCAGUGUAGUUCUCUCCUCUUCAAAUAAACAUGUCUGCCUUCAUUCUU